GUACCGGUAGCCCAGUCGAGAUGGAGGAAGAUGCGACCGGCAGACGGCAUUCGCUGGGAACGACGGAUAGACUGGGGGCUGCGGCCUAGAGGUCCGGGCUUGGAGUUCGCCUCAGACGCGGUGGAGCCGCCGGAGUCUGAGAAGGGGGCGUUAAUAACAGAGUCCAAAUUUCCGGUUGCGGCAGUACCGGGAGCCGAGUGGAUAUGGAGGAAGAUGCGACCAGCGGACGGCAUUCGCUGGGAACGACGGAUAGUCUGGGGGUUGCAUAUCAUAUACAGCAUUGAUAGGCUUUAUUAGCCCGAUUCAACAGACAAGGAAACUGAAUUUCAGUGAAGUGACUUGGUUCCAGUCUUACACUACUGAGUAAUGGAAGUGAAACUCAACAUGGAUCUCCUGAUUGCUGGUGUUCUUUCCGUUGUAUGACCUUGCCUUCUAGGUGACACUACCUUCUCUCGAGCCAGAAUCUUAUCCCAGAACCUAGUGAAUAGUCAGUCCCAUGUGAAUUUUCUGGUACAAGGAGAGUAGAGGUGGAGAGGAGGAGGCAUAUGCCCCUGGGCCUAUUUGUCCCUUUCCAUUGGUAGGGUCAAUAGUGAGAGCUCUGCCUCUAACAUUUCACUUGAUUACUUCAGGACAAAGUGCUCACUAAUUCUGCGUCACCUGUUAGGUCCCUUGAGGAAGCACGUCAACAUUUGUGCCUGAGCAGUGUUAAAAAGUGGAAGAAAAUCCGGAAUUGGAGCCAUGCACAUGAGGGUCUGAGAAAGAGCCCUAAAGAAGUUGGGCUGACUAAGUUGGGAGAAGGGAAGGCUGGAGGAACUUUGCAUACAGAGCAAGUUAUCUAAUAACUGAAGAGGACUCUGCCCUUUGGCCUGUUCCUGACUUUCUAACUCCUUUUGCUGGAGGAAGGGGAGGUUGAGGGGGGUGCCCUGUGGUGUGAAAGCCCCACUUGCCCUCUCCUCUAUACUUUCUUCCAAUGCAGACGGGAGAAAGUAUCAUAAAUGUAGUGACUGUGGGUCAGGGGAGCUCUGAGAGGCCAGCACAGGAAACCAGAAACAAAAUGAGUCAGUUCGUAGGUGGCGAUCAGAGGCACCCUGCUGAGGGUGCAAGGCCACAGGUGAUGCCUCCUCAGUAGGCCCAGGAGCAUCAAAACGGGAACAGUCCCUUUCAGCCUUCAGGAGCCUCCCAAAUGUCACUUAGUGAUGUCCCAUUCACCUGCUUAAAGGCCCUGCAUCCUGCCAGGUAGUUGGUUUGUCCAUAGCAUCCUGAGCUCUGCUUGGGUGAGCCAGACAAAAAGAAUGAUUCCUGGCCAGAGUAGUGAUACCAGGGCCCAGACAGAGGCAGAGAGUCCGGAUAGAAGAUCCUGUAAGCUGGGGUAGGGAGCCGAGGAGGCCAUGGAGCCAGGGGAAUCAUUGAAGUGAGGGACAAUUUCUGGAGGAGGGAAACUGAGUAAGGAAGGCCUGGCCAAGGACCAAGAAGGGGACAGUAUCCUGAUCUAUGAAAGAAGACUCAAGUGGGGAUUGACAGAGCCAGAUUGGGUGGAGUCCAAGCUUUGGGCAGGUCUUCAGGCACCAUGGAGGACAAACGCAACAUCCAGAUCAUCGAGUGGGAACACCUGGACAAGAAGAAGUUCUACGUGUUUGGUGUGGCAAUGACAAUGAUGAUCCGUGUCAGUGUCUACCCAUUCACCCUCAUCCGCACCCGGUUGCAAGUUCAGAAGGGGAAGAGCCUCUACCAUGGGACCUUCGAUGCCUUCAUCAAGAUCCUGCGAGCAGAUGGUAUCACUGGCCUCUACCGAGGGUUCCUGGUCAAUACCUUCACCCUCAUCUCUGGCCAGUGUUAUGUCACCACUUAUGAGCUCACCCGGAAGUUUGUAGCUGACUACAGCCAGAGUAACACAGUCAAAUCACUGGUGGCUGGUGGCUCAGCCUCCCUUGUGGCCCAGAGCAUCACAGUGCCCAUUGAUGUAGUCUCCCAGCACCUGAUGAUGCAACGCAAGGGUGAGAAAAUGGGCCGCUUUCAGGUGCGGGGGAACCCAGAGGGACAAGGGGUAGUUGCCUUUGGCCAAACCAAGGACAUCAUCAGGCAGAUCCUGCAGGCUGAUGGACUUCGCGGCUUCUAUCGAGGCUAUGUGGCUUCACUGCUUACCUAUAUCCCAAACAGUGCUGUCUGGUGGCCCUUCUAUCACUUCUAUGCAGCCAUUGUCUUUCCCUGGAUUCCAGAGCAGCUCUCCUACCUGUGUCCUAAGGAGUGCCCUCACAUUGUCUUUCAAGCUGUCUCGGGGCCCCUGGCUGCAGCCACUGCCUCCAUCCUCACCAAUCCCAUGGAUGUCAUACGAACCCGUGUGCAGGUUGAGGGCAAGAACUCCAUCAUCCUGACCUUCAGACAGCUGAUGGCAGAAGAAGGGCCUUGGGGCCUCAUGAAGGGCCUCUCGGCCAGAAUCAUCUCAGCCACACCUUCCACCAUUGUCAUUGUGGUGGGCUAUGAGAGCCUCAAGAAACUCAGCCUCCGACCUGAGCUGGUGGACUCGAGACACUGGUAACCAGUGGUGGGGAGAGAAGCCUGCUGUUUUCCACACUACCGUGGGUCAGGGGCAGAGUGGAGAGGACAGCACCCUCUCCAGGUGCUCCCACCACACACCCAGCCCUGCCCUGGGCCAAGUGGCCUAUCUGGGAUAGGGAUAGAGACUUUGAACUGCUCUUGCUGAAGAGGCUCCACGCCUGGAUCCCUUGCCCCCACUAUUUAAAAUUCUCUUCUGAGCUGGGCUCCCUCACUCAGUCCCUGUAUUUGAUACUGGCCUAAAGACCCCACCCCCCACCCUGCCAGCCCUUCUUCUGGCUUCCCCUUCCAUCUGUGUCCCUGAGACCCUGAGAAGAGCUGUACAUAGAGCUUGCUUACUACCACUGGUUCUUCCUCUUGGGCUUUCAGCCCAGACUCCAAGCAGCUGCUAUCAACCCUCUCUCCCUUCAUCUCUUAGCCUUGCUUAUUUUUAUUUUGGGACCGAGCUGCCCACUAGAUGACUCUGCUUUUCCCUGCAUUUGGGGCUAAGGUGCCAGGUACUUAUUUGCACAGGGAGCAGGAGCAGCAAAAAAUCUCUGGUUCUCCAGAGCACUCGUCCUCUCUUUGGAGGGGUUAUUAGGUUGGGAGAAAUGUUGAUACUUUUGUUUUGUGUGUGUGUGUGUGUGUGUGUGUGUGUGUGUGUGUGUGUGUGUUUUAACAUCUGUGAACCAGGCUAUUAGUCCUGCUAAAGCGCCAAUCCUGCUGUCAGAGCUCACCCCCUUCCUAAGACAGGUAGAAAAAUGUAAUGUAGCUUUUUCCACAAGCCACUUCCCUGUCCCUUCAGUCUCAGGAGCCCUAGGAGAGUCUAAGCUGGGGCAUCCCCUGGCCCAGAGGACUCCCGUGGUGGGCACAGUUCUAAGUGGAUCAGGCUGUCUUGGGUGCACUGGACUUGGAGCACUACCUUGAGAAGUCAGGUUGAGAAAGUAGUUGAUCUAGAAGGCAACAAGUGGGCAUGUGUUCCCCAGCACAUUACCCAGGCCAGCAGAGCCAAACCUAGGAGAGGGCAGUGGGUAGAUUCUCUGCCCCAGGCAGCCAUGACAUACACAUAAAUACCCCAAUCACUCAGACUUACGGCAACAAGUGUUGUCUCACUAUGGUGAUCUCUAAGAUCCACAUCACUGGAUGCGUAGUCAUCCCAGUCAUGGUACCCUGUGGAGGAAUGCUGGAAGAACAUAAAGAGCAGUUCAGAAAGUCACCCAAUACCAGGACCACUGCAUUUACCAGCCUGAUACUGCCAAGAUUAUCUGAUGCUCUCCUCAGGAGCUAGGAGAGGAGUGCUCCUUCCUCCCUACCGCUACUCUCCCCAAGCCUGUGUUGCAGGUAGAGAGGUGCAGCAAAUAGAGAAGGCAUGUCAAACCCUGCAUUUCUACCUGAGACGUGUGACCUGGAUGAUCCUCCAAACCCUAUUGGUCCCACCCCCUGGGAAAGGCCAUGGUGCCAGUUUGAAAGGUGCUAGCUACCUGAAGCCUUGAUAUUUCUUCAUGGCUGCCGCACAUUCUUCCACCUUGGCCAGAACAGGUUCUGAAAACCACUUCUCUACCUUCACCACCACCACUGCCCAUCUUGAUCUCUUUGAGGGUUUUCCCAUUUCACUUGAUCUUAUUUUUGUUUAUCCCUUCCUGCACUUUGUCAAGAGAGUCCUCCAGUUUCUAUCCAGGAAUGUUCACAUCCAAAGGGUUGGACCCACGGAUCAUUCUGAAUCUUCCUGCCCCUCCUCACUGCUUAACCCUGAGAACCACAAAUAUAAUGGAAGCAGUUCCCCCCACCCUCACCCCAUCUCUUUAAGCUCAUCCUAGCAAGACCUCUAGAGACCCUAGAGACUCGACUUUAGUCCUUCCCCGCCAUGGCACAGUGGGGAAGGUGUCAAUGGGGAGUGUCACGGACAGGAGGUAGGAUCCUGCCGCUCGCGUCUUAGUGUUUCUCCCUCAAGACUUUCCUUCUGUUUUGUUGUCUUGUGCAGUAUUUUACAGCCCCUCUUGUGUUUUUCUUUAUUUCUCGUACACACACGCAGUUUUAAGGGUGAUGUGUGUAUAAUUAAAAGGACCCUUGGCCCAUACUUUCCUAAUUCUUUAGGGACUGGGAUUGGGUUUGACUGAAAUAUGUUUUGGUGGGGAUGGGACGGUGGACUUCCAUUCUCCCUAAACUGGAGUUUUGGUCGGUAAUCAAAACUAAAAGAAACCUCUGGGAGACUGGAAACCUGAUUGGAGCACUGAGGAACAAGGGAAUGAAAAGGCAGACUCUCUGAACGUUUGAUGAAAUGGACUCUUGUGAAAAUUAACAGUGAAUAUUCACUGUUGCACUGUACGAAGUCUCUGAAAUGUAAUUAAAAGUUUUUAUUGAGCCCCCGA